GAGUGGAACAUGGCGACUUGCGCCGAAAUCCUGCGGAGCGAGUUCCCCGAAAUUGACGGACAAGUCUUCGACUACGUGACCGGCGUCUUGCACAGCGGCAGCGCGGACUUCGAGUCUGUGGAUGACCUGGUGGAAGCUGUAGGGGAACUAUUGCAAGAGGUGUCCGGGGACAGCAAGGAUGACGCGGGCAUCAGGGCCGUGUGCCAGCGCAUGUACAACACUCUGCGUCUGGCUGAGCCACAAAGCCAGGGAAAUAGCCAGGUGCUACUGGACGCCCCUAUCCAGUUGUCAAAGAUAACGGAGAACUACGGGAGAAGGUGACUGCUUUUCUUAUCGCUUACAGACUGUGGAACCAAACUUCCAGGACUGCUAAAGAGGGAACAGUCCUCGACAGUGAAUGCAAAGAAGUUAGAGAAGGCCGAGGCUCGACUUAAGGCAAAGCAGGAGAAGCGCUCAGAGAAGGACACGCUCAAGACCAGCAACCCUCUAGUCUUAGAAGAGGCAUCAGCCAGCCAGGCAGGCAGCAGAAAGGAGAGUCGGUUGGAAUCAUCUGGCAAGAACAAAUCCUAUGAUGUGCGAAUUGAGAACUUUGAUGUGUCUUUUGGCGAUAGAGUACUGCUGGCUGGAGCGGAUGUGAACCUGGCAUGGGGCCGCCGUUACGGGCUGGUGGGGCGGAAUGGGUUGGGGAAGACAACGUUACUGAAGAUGCUGGCCACCCGGAGUCUGCGGGUUCCAGCCCACAUUUCCCUGCUGCACGUUGAGCAAGAGGUUGCUGGAGAUGACACUCCUGCCCUGCAGAGUGUGCUGGAGAGUGACAGUGUGCGAGAGGAUUUGCUACGGAGGGAGCGGGAGCUCACUGCCCAGAUUGCUGCUGGCAGGGCGGAGGGCUCUGAAGCUGCAGAGCUGGCAGAAAUCUAUGCCAAACUGGAGGAGAUUGAGGCUGACAAGGCACCUGCCAGGGCAUCAGUCAUUCUCGCUGGGCUUGGCUUUACCCCUAAAAUGCAGCAGCAGCCCACCCGGGAGUUCUCAGGUGGCUGGAGGAUGAGGCUGGCCCUGGCCCGGGCCCUCUUUGCUAGGCCAGAUCUUCUGCUGUUAGAUGAACCUACAAACAUGCUGGAUGUCAGGGCCAUCCUGUGGCUGGAGAAUUACCUGCAGACGUGGCCCUCCACCAUCCUAGUCGUCUCCCACGACCGCAACUUCUUGAAUGCCAUCGCCACAGACAUCAUCCACCUGCACAGCCAGCGGCUAGAUGGUUACCGGGGAGACUUUGAGACCUUCAUCAAGAGUAAGCAGGAGCGGCUGCUCAACCAGCAGCGUGAAUAUGAGGCGCAGCAGCAGUAUCGCCAGCACAUCCAGGUUUUCAUUGACCGGUUUCGCUACAAUGCCAACAGGGCCUCUCAAGUGCAGAGUAAACUCAAGAUGCUGGAGAAGCUGCCUGAGCUGAAGCCUGUGGACAAGGAAUCAGAGGUCGUAAUGAAGUUCCCUGAUGGGUUUGAGAAGUUCUCGCCGCCAAUUCUGCAGCUAGAUGAGGUGGAUUUCUACUACGAUCCGAAGCACGUCAUCUUCAGUCGCCUCUCUGUGUCUGCUGAUCUCGAGUCUCGCAUCUGUGUGGUUGGAGAGAAUGGGGCUGGGAAGUCUACCAUGCUGAAGCUGCUUUUGGGGGACCUGGCACCUGUUCGGGGCAUCAGACACGCUCACAGGAAUCUGAAGAUUGGCUAUUUCAGCCAGCACCAUGUGGAGCAGCUGGACCUAAACGUCAGUGCUGUGGAACUGCUGGCACGCAAGUUUCCUGGGCGGCCUGAGGAGGAGUACCGUCACCAGCUGGGUCGGUAUGGCAUCUCCGGAGAACUGGCCAUGCGUCCUCUUGCCAGCCUGUCUGGGGGCCAGAAGAGCCGAGUGGCCUUUGCUCAGAUGACUAUGCCCUGCCCCAACUUCUACAUUCUGGAUGAACCCACAAACCACCUGGACAUGGAGACCAUUGAGGCUCUGGGCCGUGCCCUCAACAAUUUCAGGGGUGGUGUGAUUCUGGUGUCCCACGAUGAGCGCUUUAUCAGGCUGGUGUGCCGGGAGUUGUGGGUAUGCGAAGGAGGCGGCGUCACCCGUGUGGAAGGAGGAUUUGACCAGUACCGCGCCCUCCUCCAGGAACAGUUCCGCCGCGAAGGCUUCCUCUAGGGCCACCAGGCUGAGGACUCGCCCAGGACAUGGACUGGUCUCUCAGACCCCUGGGCCACCAUGUAGGCCACCACUCCAGGCCGUGGACUUCCCCCAACUUGGGGACAGCCUUAUUCCCAAAUGUCUCUAUCCUUUUGACUGGAGCAUCUUCUGCACAACCUUGGGAGCCCAUCCAAGGGUUGGUGAGGACUGGUCUCCCGGGGGUGGGGGUCUGGGGGGUACCCUCUGGGGUUAUAGAUUCCCCCACUGCCCCAGCUCUGACUGGACCCCAAGUGGCUGCUAUGUAAAUUAAAUCUCUCCCCGCGUC